AGCAGCAGGAGGAGGCAGAGCACAGCAUCGUCGGGACCAGACUCGUCUCAGGCCAGUUGCAGCCUUCUCAGCCAAACGCCGACCAAGGAAAACUCACUACCAUGAGAAUUGCAGUGAUUUGCUUUUGCCUCCUAGGCAUCACCUGUGCCAUACCAGUUAAACAGGCUGAUUCUGGAAGUUCUGAGGAAAAGCAGCACUAAAGAUGUACCUACCCCUCCACAACAGAUGAAACUGUGCCAGCCAAACAACAAAUGGGCAUUGUCCCCAGAAGCUUGGACAAAAAGGCACACAGAGUUCAAUUCCAGUUGAACAGAAUAAAGGCCAAAAUAGAGCUGCCUUGGGGGUCACUGCAAUUAGACUGCUUAAUGAAGACAUUAAAAGAACUUUACAACAAAUACCCAGAUGCUGUGGCCACAUGGCUAAACCCUGACCCAUCUCAGAAGCAGAAUCUCCUAGCCCCACAGAAUGCUGUGUCCUCUGAAGAAACCAAUGACUUUAAACAAGAGACCCUUCCAAGUAAGUCCAACGAAAGCCAUGACCACAUGGAUGAUAUGGAUGAUGAAGAUGAUGAUGACCAUGUGGACAGCCAGGACUCCAUUGACUCGAACGACUCUGAUGAUGUAGAUGACACUGAUGAUUCUCACCAGUCUGAUGAGUCUCACCAUUCUGAUGAAUCUGAUGAACUGGUCACUGAUUUUCCCACGGACCUGCCAGCAACCGAAGUUUUCACUCCAGUUGUCCCCACAGUAGACACAUAUGAUGGCCGAGGUGAUAGUGUGGUUUAUGGACUGAGGUCAAAAUCUAAGAAGUUUCGCAGACCUGACAUCCAGUACCCUGAUGCUACAGACGAGGACAUCACCUCACACAUGGAAAGCGAGGAGUUGAAUGGUGCAUACAAGGCCAUCCCCGUUGCCCAGGACCUGAACGCGCCUUCUGAUUGGGACAGCCGUGGGAAGGACAGUUAUGAAACGAGUCAGCUGGAUGACCAGAGUGCUGAAACCCACAGCCACAAGCAGUCCAGAUUAUAUAAGCGGAAAGCCAAUGAUGAGAGCAAUGAGCAUUCCGAUGUGAUUGAUAGUCAGGAACUUUCCAAAGUCAGCCGUGAAUUCCACAGCCAUGAAUUUCACAGCCAUGAAGAUAUGCUGGUUGUAGACCCCAAAAGUAAGGAAGAAGAUAAACACCUGAAAUUUCGUAUUUCUCAUGAAUUAGAUAGUGCAUCUUCUGAGGUCAAUUAAAAGGAGAAAAAAUACAAUUUCUCACUUUGCAUUUAGUCAAAAGAAAAAAUGCUUUAUAGCAAAAUGAAAGAGAACAUGAAAUGCUUCUUUCUCAGUUUAUUGGUUGAAUGUGUAUCUAUUUGAGUCUGGAAAUAACUAAUGUGUUUGAUAAUUAGUUUAGUUUGUGGCUUCAUGGAAACUCCCUGUAAACUAAAAGCUUCAGGGUUAUGUCUAUGUUCAUUCUAUAGAAGAAAUGCAAACUAUCACUGUAUUUUAAUAUUUGUUAUUCUCUCAUGAAUAGAAAUUUAUGUAGAAGCAAACAAAAUACUUUUACCCACUUAAAAAGAGAAUAUAACAUUUUAUGUCACUAUAAUCUUUUGUUUUUUAAGUUAGUGUAUAUUUUGUUGUGAUUAUCUUUUUGUGGUGUGAAUAAAUCUUUUAUCUUGAAUGUAAUAAGAAUUUGGUGGUGUCAAUUGCUUAUUUGUUUUCCCACGGUUGUCCAGCAAUUAAUAAAACAUAACCUUUUUUACUGCCUA